GAGGCGCUUGGAAACCACCGUCAAUUGGACCGCACUGGGAAACACAGAUGAACAAAGUCAACACCGCUUUGUCCUUCAGUGCCUGGCUCCUUUUUCAGCUCGUCUUGCGACUCCAGGUACUGGAGUCCAGGGAGGGGCAAAAGGCCUCUGAGGGAGUAUUACAGCCGCCUCAUCCACCAGAAGCAUUUCCAGCAGAUCCAGGUCUGCACCCCCUGACUGCAGGGCCAAGGACUACCCCCGCUUCUAGGGUUGGUGGACCUGGGUGUCUCUCUGGACACAUCCUCCAGUGGCCUGGACCUGCCCAUGAAGGUGGUGGACAUGUUCAGGUGCUGUUUGCCUGCGUGUGCCGUGAACUUCAAGUGGCAAGCUAAACCAGUUCUGGAAGAACCUGCAAGAGUCUCAGCAGCUCUGAUGGGAUGAGAGCUGGGUGCAGACUGUGCUCCCUUUGGUUAUGGACACAUAACUCCUGGGCCAGAGGCUAAAACCCCAGGGCCCCUGCUGUCCUUCCCGCAGCUUCUUGGAGUCUCAGGGCAAAGCCUUUCGAGCAGCGCCUCCCAGUGGCCAGAAGCUGAAAUGACGGCAGUGGUGUCACCUGGUGAAUGACCCGGGAAGCUGUGGUUGGCCCUGAUUUCUUCUUUGGAGUCUCUGAAAUGCUUCCUGUCUUCUGUUCUUCAUGCCCCAUGCCCCUGCUAGCGUAUUACUGUUCUGUGACUUCCCUGUGACCUCUGCAGUACUCCUCAUCCUGCAUUUGGUCUCCAGGUGUCACCUUUCUGCCAUGUUCCUAACACUUUCAUUCCUGUCUUGAAAAAAGCGCCUGCUGCACCAUAAGCCCUGGGAUGUGGCAGCUGCAGCGGGCUUGGCUUUGUGAGGAACCGAGUGUGUCCAGGGAUGUGGCAGCUGCAGCGGGCUUGGCUUUCUGAGGAACCGAGUGUGUCCACGUUGGGGGAACGUCAUCCUUGAUACACACGUUUUUAUUUGCAGAAAGAAAAUGCUAUUUUUGGA